AGAUUUUUGACAUGUUAUAAAAUGCAAGUCACAGCUGCUGUUGUCUGCGGUAUUCAAAAACUUUUGAAACACUGCAUGUCCAACAAAAUUUAUUUUUUGUGUGAAUGUAAGUUUUUAUUGAGGGUAAGUCCUGUUUGUUUGGAAAAAAGAAACAGUAUGAGUCAGUGCUUUUUAAAAAUCAAAUAGAUUUAAUGUUCUCCUUCCUGCCUGUUCUCGCUCGUGUGUGUUUCUCUCGAUUGCUUGCUCGCUUUCUCUGCCUCUCUGCUUGUCUAAGAAAGAGCUGUUGGCUUUGAGAGAAGACCUUGGUAUUACAACUGUGUUAGUAGAUUGAGAUUUCUGUUAGAGUCUUUCUGUUUAGGUCAGAAGUGUUCUUUAUAGAACAGAACUGGGAGCUUGUAAUCAUAAUGUACUGUUUUUCAACCCUACUCUCUUGACCAAGAAUGAAACUAUUUACAAAUUAAGAUGCCAACAGAUCACGAAGAGCCCUGUGGUCCCAGUCACAAGUCGUUUUGCCUGAAUGGGGGGCUUUGUUAUGUGAUACCUACUAUUCCCAGCCCAUUUUGUAGGUGCGUUGAAAACUAUACAGGAGCUCGUUGUGAAGAGGUUUUUCUCCCAGGCUCCAGCAUCCAAACUAAAAGUAACCUGUUUGAAGCUUUUGUGGCAUUGGCGGUCCUAGUAACACUUAUCAUUGGAGCCUUCUACUUCCUUUGCAGGAAAGGCCACUUUCAGAGAGCCAGUUCAGUCCAGUAUGAUAUCAACCUGGUAGAGACGAGCAGUACCAGUGCCCACCACAGUCAUGAACAACACUGAAGAAACGUCAAAGUGAACCAAAUCAUUGUUUUUAUUUUACAAAGGCAGAAAAUGAAACACCACUAGGUAAAAGAAUUAAAAAUCUAAUCCUUUAUUUCUUAAAUAAAACGCUUGUGUAACUCGUAUCAUGAACCAUAAUCCAUUCUGCUGCAAGGUGUGUGUGCUUCUGUAAUGUGCAUCAGUCCAUCGGCAACUGCUAAGUAGGGGGUGAUACCAGUAUAAUUCGAAGUCACAUUGGUUCAACAUGACUCUCCCCAGAAAGCUGAUGUGCUGAAGCAACCAGAGGCAAAUGUUCACACACCUAGAGAGAAACCCUAAGGGAUAUAUGAAGAUCUUAUGAAAAAGGAUGAAAACCCUUUAAAUGCAAGGAGUAGCUGGCUUAGUGGCUUCAAAACCACCUCAUUCCUGCUGUUAUCUGAGAAGCUGCAAGUACUGAUGAAAAAACUGAGAAGACAUUUCACCUGGCAAUUAGAAAAAAGCGCUGACUGAUAGAUACCUCUGUAUCAUUCUUUCAAUAUUGAUGAAAAUGCUUUCUACUAGAAGUGACUGAUUUCAAGGAUCUGUCUCUCAAAGGAAGAAACAAAAACCCAAAAUUUUGACUGCAAAAGAUUGACUAAUUCUAGGUGCAAGUAACUGGAAAUUUAGGAUUGUUAUUGUACUACACAGGUCACAAAGUUCCAAACCUAUUUCCCUUGUAAUUUUUAGUGCAUGAUUUUUCAGAAUGCAGUUUCUAUCUUUUUAGGUGCAAUAUUAAGAACUGAUUAGGUCAGAACAAUUUAGUUUCUCCAGUUUUUUCUACCUAAGUUACAUGGGGGAAAAAAAAGCAAUAGUAACUUUAAGGAAGUAUGAAAAUAAAGUCUUGGAGCAGUGGAAAGGUCUGGGGCUGGUAAAUGGCUUAGGCAGAAGGGCAUGCACCGGCCAAACCUAACAGCCUGUCUCUGAACUAUGUCCUCGUCAAGGCUGGGAUGCACGCUGGCUUCUCUACACAGUCUGGCCCAGUGUAAGUGCUGUGAAUUCAGUGGGUCACUAGUGUCACCAAUUCAUUCAUCACCCAUCAUUCACUCAUUUCACAAACACAUGAGGGUAAGACAUUGAGACAGAGUACACAAAAUGAAAAGCUCUCACAUAAUUUUAAUAGACUUUAUUAGAAGUUUUAGAUUUUCAGAAAAACUGAGCAGAUAGUAUAGAGUUCCCCUAUGCUUCCCCCCACCCCAGGCCUUUAUUAUUAACAUCUUGCACUAGUGUGGUAUAUUUGUUUAACCAAUAUUGACACAUUUUUACUUUACUUUUUGAGACAAAGUCUCACUCUGUCAUCCAGGCUAGCUGAAGCCUGUAAUUUACAUGAAGGGUCCUCUUUUUGUUGUAUGUCUUUAUGGAUUUUGACCAAUAUAUAAUGUCAUGUAUCCACUAUUAUAGUAUUGUAUACAGUAGUUUCACCACCCUAAAAAUCUCUACUCCAUGUAUUUACCCCUCCCUCUCUCCCACUGAACCUCUGGCAACCAGUCUUUACUAACUUUGCUUUCUCCAGAAUGUCAUAUAUUUGAAAUCAUGUAGUAUGUAGCCUUUCAGACUAACUUCUUUCACUUAGCAAUAUACACUUAAAGUUCCUCUAUGUCUUGUGACUAAAUACCCCACCCCCUGCCCUUUUUAAAAAAAAAAAAAAAAGCUAGGCCAUAUUUUUUUUUUUUUUUUUUUUUGGUGGUUUAAAAAUUUACUGUGGCAAAAUGUACGUAAGAUUUAAAUUUUAACCAUUUUGAAGUUACAGUUUAAAGGCAUUAAAUACAUUCGUUGUAUGUACCAGUCACCACUAUGCACCUCCGGAACUUUUUCAUGAUCCCACACUAAUCUCUGUGCCCCUUAAACAAUAAAUUCCCAUUCCCUCCUGCUCCCUGUGACAAAACGUAAUCUUUGUUCUACUUUGUCUCUAUGAAUCUCACUAGUCUAGGUACCUCACAUCAGUGGAUUCAUAUAGUAUUGUCCUUUUGUGAUUUACUUAAUGUCUGAAAGGUUCAUCCAUGAUGUAGUAUGUAGAAGGAUUUCCUUUUUAUGGCUGAAUAAUAUUCCAUUGUAUGGAUAUAACACAUUUUGUCUAUCCAUUCAUCUGUUGGGUAUUUGGGUUGUUUCUACCUUUUGACUACGGUGAAUAAUGCUGCAGUGAACACUGGUAUACAAAUAUACCCUCAAGCCUCCGCUUUCAAUUAUUUUGUGUAUAUACCCAGAAAUGCAAUUGCUGAAUCAAAUGACAAUUCUAUAUUUAAUUGGAAAAUCACCAUACUGUUUUCUACAGCAGCUGCAUACCACUAUAUUUCCAUCAGUAAUAAGAGUUCCAAUUUCUCCACAUCCUUGCCAACACUUGUGUGUUUUUUUAAUUUUAAUAAGAGCUAUCCCAGUGGGUAUGAAGUGGUAUCUCAAUGUGGUUUUGAUUUGCAUUUCCUUACUGUUUAGUGAUGCUAAGCAUUUUUUCCUGUGCUCACUGGCUAUCUGCAUGUCCUCUCUGGAGAUCUAUCCAAAUCCUUUGCCAUUUUUUAAAUCAGGUUUUUACACUGUUGUUGCAUUUUGGGAGUUUUGUAUGUAUUCUGGAUGUUUAAUCCUUAUUAGGUACGUGAACUGCAUAUUAUUUCCUCCCACUCCAUAGGUAAUCUUUUUACUCUGUUGAUAGUGUUCUUUGAUGCACAAAAUUUUAAUGAAGUAUAAUUUGCCUA